ACUCCCUUCCCCUUCUCUGCUCAUGCAGGGAGCCCAGGAAGCCUCCGCCUCAGAGAUGCUACCGCUGCUGCUGCCCCUGCUGUGGGCAGGGGCCCUGGCUCAGGAGCGGAGAUUCCAGCUGGAGGGGCCAGAGUCACUGACGGUGCAGGAGGGUCUGUGCGUCCUCGUACCCUGCAGAUUGCCCACUACCCUUCCAGCCUCGUACUAUGGUUAUGGCUACUGGUUCCUGGAAGGGGCUGAUGUUCCAGUGGCCACAAACGACCCAGACGAAGAAGUGCAGGAGGAGACCCGGGGCCGAUUCCACCUCCUCUGGGAUCCCAGAAGGAAGAACUGCUCCCUGAGCAUCAGAGAUGCCCGGAGGAGGGACAAUGCUGCAUACUUCUUUCGGUUGAAGUCCAAAUGGAUGAAAUACGGUUAUACAUCUUCCAAGCUCUCUGUGCGUGUGAUGGCCCUGACCCACAGGCCCAACAUCUCCAUCCCAGGGACCCUGGAGUCUGGCCAUCCCAGCAAUCUGACCUGCUCUGUGCCCUGGGUCUGUGAGCAGGGGACGCCCCCCAUCUUCUCCUGGAUGUCAGCUGCCCCCACCUCCCUGGGCCCCAGGACCACCCAGUCCUCGGUGCUCACAAUCACCCCACGGCCCCAGGACCACAGCACCAACCUCACCUGUCAGGUGACGUUCCCUGGAGCCGGUGUGACCAUGGAGAGAACCAUCCAGCUCAAUGUCUCCUGGAUGUUGAGGCGGCCACCUCUUUCCACCCCAGAUGCUCCACAGAAAGUGGCCAUCAGCAUCUUCCAAGGAAACAGCGCAGCCUUCAAAAUCCUGCAAAACACCUCGUCCCUCCCUGUCCUGGAGGGCCAGGCUCUGCGGCUGCUCUGUGAUGCUGACGGCAACCCCCCUGCACACCUGAGCUGGUUCCAGGGCUUCCCCGCCCUGAACGCCACCCCCAUCUCCAAUACCGGGGUCCUGGAGCUGCCUCAAGUAGGGUCUGCAGAAGAAGGAGAUUUCACCUGCCGUGCUCAGCAUCCUCUGGGCUCCCUGCAAAUCUCUCUGAGUCUCUUUGUGCAUUGGAAACCAGAAGGCAGGGCUGGUGGUGUCCUGGGAGCAGUCUGGGGAGCUAGCAUCACAACCCUGGUUUUCCUCUGUGUUUGCUUCAUCUUCAGAGUGAAGACUAGAAGGAAGAAAGCAGCCCAGCCAGUGCAAAACACGGAUGAUGUGAACCCCGUCAUGGUCUCAGGCUCCAGGGGUCAUCAGCACCAGUUCCAGACAGGCAUAGUUUCAGACCACCCUGCUGAGGCUGGCCCCAUCUCAGAAGAUGAGCAGGAGCUCCACUACGCUGUCCUACACUUCCACAAGGUGCAACCUCAGGAACCAAAGGUCACCGACACUGAGUACUCAGAAAUCAAGAUACACAAGUGAGGAAUUGUCCAAAGCCAUAACCUUGAUUGGAGAGAACAUGGUACCUCUCAGUGUAUUGGUUACUAGGGCUGCCACAGCAAUGUACCACAAACCGAGUGACAUAAACACAGAACUUUAUUUUCGUAUAGUUUCAGAUGUUAGAGGUCUGAGAACAAGGUGUUAUCAGGGUUGGUCCCUUCUAAGGCCUCUCUUGUUGGCUUGUAGAUGGCUGUCUCCUCCUUGUGUCUUCACAUGGUCUUUCCUCUGAGUGUGUUUGUGUCCUAAUCUUCUCUUCUUAUAAAGACACUAGUCAUAUUGGAUUAGGGCCUCCCCAUGACCUAAUUUAAAUAAAUUAACUAUUUAAAGACCCUCCAAAUACAGUAACCUUCUGAGAUAUUGAGAUUUAGGACUUCCAACAUAUGAAUUUUAGAAGGGAACAAUUUAGCCCAUAACACUGUGUCCAAUUCUUUUAAAAUUAAUGUUUUUGUUGUAAAUGGACUAUAUAAAUACCUUCGUAUAUAUGGCAGACCACAGGACUUCUGUCCAAGAGAACUGAGUUCAACUCCAUCUAUGCCAGCUAUUGAGCAAGUCGCUUUAUGUCCCUGCUCUGUAAGGCAGGGAAAUAAUUUCCAUCUAACCAGAUUAUUGUGAAAGGUCAAAGAAAGCAUACAGCUAACAUACAGCUUUGUUAGCUGUAAAACAGCUAACAAAGGCCCUGACACAAAGGUUUUCAUAAAGUCUGUAUAUUUUUGUAAAUGAAUGCCUUGUAUCUGGCUUUGGCUAGCUUUUUUUUUUUUUUUUUUUUUCUGAGAUGGAGUCUUGCUGUAUCUCCCAGGCUGGAGUGCAGUGGUGCGAUCUUGGCUCAGUGCAAGCUUCGCCCCCUGGGUUCACACCAUUCUCCUGCCUCAGCCUCCCAAGUAGCUGGGACUACAGGCACCCACCACCACACCCGGCUAAUUUUUUGUAUUUUUAGUAGAGACGGGGUUUCACCGUGUUAGCCAGGAUGGUCUUGAUCUCCUGACCUCGUGAUCUGCCCUCCUCGGCCUCCCAAAGUGCUGAGAUUACAGGCAUGAGCCACCGCACCCGGCUUUGAUUAGCUGUUUUAACAGACGGUUUCUGCUGGCAAUUUCUUCUAAGGCUGAAAAGGAGUAGGCCCAGAGGCCACAGCACCAGGUGUCUGUGUCACCCCCUGUUCAGAACUCUUCACGACUCCCCAAAAUAAGGUUUCCAUCCAUCAUCUUUCUGCUCAAGGCUCUCUACAUGAUCUUGUCCAUCCAGAUUUCCCCAGAUCAAUUCCUCACCAGUCACCAAUACCCCAUGUCCAUUUCCACAGCUUCCUCUUACAAAUCCCAGUCUCCACUAUUCCAGUGAAAUUGAAGAAAGCAUUUAAUGAAGACCAACUAUUAAGGAAAAUUCUUAAGAGUAGCCAUGAAAAAUAAAAAGAUAGAUUACACUUAAAAGACCACAGUUAGCAGUGGCUCACGCCUGUAAUCCCAGCACUUUGGGAGGCUGAGGUGGGUGGAUCACUGGAGGUCAGGAGUUCGAGACUGGUCUGGCCAACAUGGUGAAACCCCAUCUCUACUAAAAUACAAAAAUUAGCUCGGUGUGGUGGCACUUGCCUGUAAUCCCAGGUACUUCUGCAGGUUGAAGCAGGAGAAUUGCUUGAACCUGGGAGGUGGAGGUUGAAGUGAGCUGAGAUUGCAUCACUGCACUCCAGCCUGGGCAACAGAGCGAGACUCCAACUCAGAAAAAGCAAAACAAAACAAACAAACAAGCAAAAAACCACAAUUAGACUGACAGCUGACUUUUUUAGGAGCAAUAUUGGAAGGCUAAAUGCAAUAGAAAGAUGUCUUUGAUGGCUUAAGAGAAAUAAAUGUUGUUUUAGAAAGCCUACUCAAUGAAAACACAUUUUAAGACUGAAAGUGAAAUAUAGAUAUUUUAAGGAAAACCAAAAUAUGUGAGUGUUAAUAAAGAAAAGAUUUCUCAAAUAAAUUCUAAAACAUAUAAUUCAGGUAUUAGGAAAGUGAUCCCAGAUUAGAUUUUUGAGAUCCAAAAAAAAUGAAAACCUAGGAAAGUAGCAAAUAUGUGAGCAAAAUGAAACAAAUACUUGUUGUAAAAAUGAUGGUUUGUAGAGGGGUCAAACAUCAAAUGUAAUAUUGAAAUACCAAUAUUAUAUAGCCCAGAAACUAUAAUAACAUAAAGUUCAGAAGAGUGUAAAUAGAAUUUAUAUUACAUAAAGUCUUUAUAUUUUUCCAGAGAAAAUUAAAUGUUAUGAUGAAUGUUA